ACUGCCCCCACAGUUUCUCUCUGCUUCUGGUCAGCUGGGUUGUCCUGCAUGGUGACGGGUGUCAUCCCGAACAAAUCAGAUGGCAUCAGAGGCACUCCAUCAAGUGGGAGAUGGGGAGGAGGCUGUACUGAAGAAAGAAAACUUCAACAUGAUGAAUGCCCUUGACCAACUGCCAAAACCCUUUUCAAACCCCAAGUCUAUGAACCGGACCGUCACUACCAAAGGACUCCCACUAGCCUCAAAGGGCAAUUUGGUCAACUUCUUGGAGGAUGAUACCAUCAACCUACUGAAGCCGCUGCCAGUAGAGGAUUCAGACUGCAGCUCUGAUGAGACCAGCAUCUCUGCCUUCUCAUCCACCUUGCUGAACCCCAUCAAAUUAGCUGUGACCCAGCCCAACAGCAGCUUCUUUGCAGGGAUGCUGGAGGGGGAGCUGAACAAACUCAGCUUCUCCCCAAUGGCCAAGAAUGCAGAAAAUGAGGACCUGGCGCUCGGCCCCUGCCCAUGCCCAUCGAAGUCCCAGAUGGCCACAAGGGGCCUGCUGGACCUUGACAACCCUGAGCUGGAGACAGAAACCUCCUCAACGCACUCAGAAUCUUCUGUGGUUGUGGACCUGCCGGACACCCCCUUCAUCUUUGAGCACACCGUCAACAAUUCCACAGCUGUGAUUUCCUGGACCUACGCCUUGGGCAAGCAGCCGGUCAGUUUCUACCAGCUCCUGUUACAGGAGGUGGCCAAGACACAGGAGAAUGAGUUGCCCGAGGCAAAGAAUCGUCCAUGGAUCUUCAACAAGAUUUUGGGCACUACUGUCAAGCUGAUGGAGCUAAAGCCUAACACGUGUUACUGCCUCAGUGUCCGUGCAGCCAACACAGCUGGGGUGGGGAAGUGGUGCAAGCCCUACAAAUUUGCAACCCUGGCCACUGACUUCAGCAGCUUUCCUGAGAACUACCCCAUCCAGAUCACCGUGCGGCGCAAGGAACCCCGGCAAAAGAUCGUGUCCAUCGGGCCGGAGGAGAUGCGGAGGCUGGAGGAUCUGGAAUACCUAUUUCCCUGUUAAGGGGGAGGGCCCCAGGACACCCCUCACCUACUUUCAGCUUCAACCCCAGGCCCUCAGAAACCAGAGCCAUGAGACCUACCAUACCACCAGCACCCUGCGGGCCCGGGGUCUGGCAGAGUGGUAUGGGCACCCCACCCCUGGGCUGGGGCCAAGGCUACAUAGGGGCCCCAUUCACCUGGAGGCAUCUCAGGCCAGGCCAUGCCAGGCUCAGCCACUGCCCACAGCUGCUAGACUCCCUCCUCCUCCAAAUCUGGGCUGGGUCUAGGUCCCUCAUUAAAGAACUGCAGGUCAUCCAGCA